CUUUUUCAUUUCUUGGCCUCAGCAGGUAAGGGUGAGCUUAUGCAGUUCCAAGAUGUUCUUUCUGAGAUACUUACAGAUUAUUAACGCCGUUGUAUGGGAUGAUAAUUACUAGCAGCCAUGUUCUUUCUUGAUUUCUCAUUCUUUCCCAAUCCUUGCACUGAUAACUUGUUUAACAAACUUCCAAAAUGAAGUGGAAACAAUGUUUUCUUUUCCUUUUUUAGCAUGUUUUCUUGGAGGUGCACAUGCCUAAGAAUUGUAUGCACUAUUUCUCUAAAGCCCUAAGUUAUAUCUUAUAUUUAAAAAUUUAAAAAAAAUAUAACUCCACAUCUGUGCGGAAAAACUUUUGAUAAUUUGUGGCAAAAAUGCCAUGCUUAGCUUUUAAGUUGUUUUGUUCCUAGAAAGUACUCUGCCAACAUUCUUUACAAAAUGUUAAACUGCUUGUAAUGUUAUACUUUAACAAAGGAAAGGCACAAUUAGUCUACACAUUCUCCUACUUCCCUGCCCAAACACAUGCAUCCAAAGAUCAAUUUGAAAAAAUGUUCAUUUUUUUUUUUAAUGCUCAAAACAGGUAUGCUAUAGACAUCUAAUUCCAUUUUGCCUUGCAAGGAACUGUUAAAACUCUUCUGAACAAAAUAGUACAGAAAUAGGUCAUUUAACAUACUUGUUUUUAAUUGUGUUUUUUAAAAAAUAUUUUAAACUUUGUAAGUUAUCAGACUUUAGUCAAUUCCAAAAUACCUUUAGGAUUCCAGUGAUUUUUGAGUUUGUGUUGGGAGUUGAAAUGGUUUUCUCUUACUAAAAUCUAUUUUAUGUGCUGUUUAAAUUUCUGUUAACUGAGCUAUCAAGCAAAUCCUGUAAGGUGAAUUUUUCCCAUUUACUGUGAGAAAGGAAUACUGGUGGAAACCCCUAUCAUGUGAUGGACCUUGUAGUUCCAGCAGUGAUGCUGGGCUGCUAAAAUAAUAAUCUUUCACUUAAUCUUCCCUUCUUUCAUCACACAUUUAAAAAUUACCUUUAAGCCUUUUCAAUUUAGUAUCUCUUUCAGCAUAGUUGUCCAGUCUCAAAUUCCUUGAAGGUGUGCAUUAAUGUACAUUUAUCGACAUGUCCUUUGUUUAUUCAAAUUAAGCAAAUACAGUUGAGAAUUUGUUGUUGCUUUGUUUCUUUUAAAAAAUUAAAUAAAAAAAUAUUUCCUGUUGGGAGACAUUUUGGGAAUCACUGAAAAAAAUUAAGAAAGUAAAAAUCACCGUCAUAUCAUCUAAAAAGAAACAACUGGUAAUUAGAUGAUGUGCUUCCAUUUUACUCUGUUUGUCUGCAUAGACAUACUUUUGAACAAAAUUGGCCUUUAAUUUUAUCUGUAGUUUUAAAUAUUGCACUUUUAUUUAAUAUGAAGUAAAUAUUAGAGACGUUUCCUUUUUCUGUAAACCCUUUGAAAAUAAGAUUUUUAAUGAUGAAUACACCCAAGUUUAUUGAACUAGUUUUCUGUUGUUUUACGUAUUAUUUUUAGUUUUAGUGGCUUGAGAAUACAGUAUUAAACCCUUUGGUUGCCAAUCCUAGCACGGCCACUUCCUAAGUGACCUUAAUUACCUCUUUAAUCGCAUUUCCUUGGAAUAAGGGUCAUGGUGCCUGCACCAUAGAGUUUUGGUGAGAUGGAAUGAACUAAGUAGAGGAAGGCCAGCAGGGUCGACCAAAUGACGUAGGCUCAGUACGUAAGAGUGGACACACAGGUGGAGCUGAGAAAAAUGCCCUUGUCUGAAAGUUUAAAUAUUUCGGAUUUACUCAGGUUAGAUUUAUAGCAGUGGAAAUCCUGGGGCAGAGGUGAACUCUUUUAUGACUCUUGUGGCUUGUUGCCAAAUUGCUUAUGCCAUAACAUUCCCUUACAGAGUGUAUGGUCUACCUGUAGUGUGUCAGCACUCCAGUGUUCAUCAUCUUUCCUGAUUUUUCUAUAAAAAUAUGAUCUUUUAAUUUAUUUUUUGGUAGCUAUUGAAAUUGAUCAUCUGUUUUUUUUCUUUUGUUUUCCUUUUUGGGAGCUCUCUCUUCUGGUACUUUGCCUACUUUAAAGUGGUGAUUUAAAAAAAUUAAAUACCCGUUUUAUCUAAAGAAGAUUGAGUGUUUAUCAUGUUUUUAGUUUUCUUUUUUUUCUUCUCCACAGGCCAUUAUUUCUUUCACUUUUUGGCGUUUUUCAACCAAUAAAAUAUUUUUAUUUCUAUAUAAACAAGUCUCUACCUUGUCCUUUAUGAUUUUUUCCUUGUAUUUGUUCAUGCUUGGAAAGCCCAGAAAGACCCUGCAAAUGGCCCCAGUGAAAAACUCAGGAGAAGCAGUAAGCAGUCAAAAGUGGAUGGGGAGGAAGACUAAGGCGUUGAGGAAGACCACUUAUUUUACAAUAAGGCUUUUAGACUUUAAAGCUGUAUGCAUAUAUUAAAUUUAAUAAUCUUUAUCUGAAAGGUGAGAUAAACAACAUUUUGGAAAUAUGUUAGAUCUUUUUACAUUUAAUUCUAUAAUUGUACAUGGAUAUGAAGCGCUCCUAUACCGCCGCUGCCUCCUCUUCCUUUUCCCUAGUUAGCGAGUUCUACCACCAUUUGUUAAAUAGUUCCUCCUUUCUUCUUUGCUUUGUGGUCUUUAUUGUUUUUUAAGAUCUUGACUAACUUUGAGGUCUGCUUCAGUUUUAGGUCUUGCUUCUCUGUGUGUUGAUCCUCUAGUCUUAAUCAAUGCCACAUCUUUUUAAUCAUAGAUUUAGAAUAUUUAGAAAUACCUGGCAGAGCAAGUCACACUAUCCUUUUAACAUUACAAUUCUAUGCCCUUGUCCUUUCAGAUAAAGAUUAUUGUAUUUAAUACAUGCACAGUUUUAAAAGUCUAGGAGGCUUAUUGUAAAAUAGAUGGUCUUUCAUCUGCCUCUUCUUCCCCCCAUCCCUUACUCUCCCUCCCCAGUGGCAGCUACUUUGGAUUGUUUACUGUUUCUCCUGCGUUUUUCACUGGGGCCAUUUGUAGGGUCUUCUUGGGCUGGUCAGAGAGUGGUCUUCCAGUAAAGUUUUGCACUGAGGAAAGAGUGUAGGUUCCAGUGUUCAUGGAGGAAUCUGGCUGGGGUUUCAGCAUUCUCUGUGUAGAGUCAUGUUGGAGAAGGUUCACCAUACAGACUUACCUGUUUACCUACUCUUCCAAGAACAAAUCUCUAGUCUUGCUAGGUUCUAGGAUUGUCUGCCAAUGGUCUACAGUGAGGAGGUGGGGAAGGCAUCUUGGAAUUUUAGAGCUUCUCAUGCAGCUUUUACUGACCUUAUUUUAACCUGUCACCCUUUUACCCUCAGUCUUUGAGCAGACUGGAGUGAGUACUUCUCGGCUUUUCUCACUGUUGGUAUAGCAUUCCCUCUCUCAAGUUGGCUGAGACAGUUGCCACUUGUCCAUCUGUUUUCCACUUUCAUGAUUUGUAGUUUCCAUUACAGUUCUUUAAGUCCUUGGGUCUCUAUGUCUUCUAGAAAGAUCUCUUACUGUCACUUAAGUGGGGUUUAGGGAAAGGGUGUAAUUGGAUAUGUGUGUUAAAUUUACCGUCUUAAUCUGGAAGGCUCGGAAGAUGAAUCCUUAGAACUAAAAAAAUACCGGAUCAUGUUACAUUUUGUUUCGUUGGCAAGGACUGCCAUCUGUAAUCAGUGUUUCUUUUAAGGGUCAUGAAAGAUUAUUCAUGACCUUUUAUCUCUCAGCAGAGUUGUUUUCUUCAUCUGAAUCCUAAUGUUUCCUGUUAGAGUUCUUCUUAGGUAUUUGUUUUUGUUACUUUGUGAUGGGCUCUUCAAAUUGGCUGUCGGUAGUCUAAGAUGGUGGUUGAUUUUGGUGUAUUUAUUUUAUAGCUGGCACUUAUGCGAAAAGCUUUGCAGUUUAUUUUUGUAUGUUCCCAAGUUAUAUGAGUGGCAGAUAAUGACACUUUUAUCUACUUUUAAAUAGUUAUGACUUUUAUUUUGGUUCUGUGGCGGUUUGCACUAGAUUUAGCAUUCUGUAACGUUAUAACAUCUUUCUGGAACAUUAUCGAAUAGUAAUGGUGAUAAUGUACACACUUUUAUUGUUCUUUAUUUUAGUAAGGAAAAGAAUAGUAGAAUAUUGGCUUUUUGGUUUAUCAUAAUUCUUCAUCAGGACAAAGAAAAUCUAUCCUUUCAUUUCCAAGUUGCCUAGAGGUAAUUUUAUGUUUUUAAGACAUGGGAAUUGAAUAUUAGCAAGUGAUCAUUAGCAUCUGCAGUUUAUCUGCUGGUAUUUCUGAAGAGUCUACUGAUUUGAGUCCCAAAUAUUAAAUUGGAUCAAAAUUUUCCUUAUGGAUGGUUCUUCAGAAAAAGAAAUUGAAUGCAUGGGAAGAAUGUAGUAUAACAUAUUCAAUGCAUGAGCAUAUUGUCUUGGUUGGGGUGGUAUAGGAGAUGUCACUAGGGAUUUUUCACAAGCAAAUAUUCCAAGUUAUAGCUGACACUCAAGUCACAUCUUUACCUGUUGGCAGUAUUUGAUGUAAUUUGUUAUUCCUCCUUUUUUAAUAUUCUUCCUUCAUUUGAUUCUUGAGGACACCACACACUGUUGCCUUCCCUUCUAUACCGCUGGCCUUCUGGUUUCUUUUCAGUUGUUUUUAAAUUUGUGUUGGUUUUCUCUUCUCACCAGCCUAUGAAUUUAGAAUGUGCCAAGGCUCAGUUCUCACCCGCCUGUUGUCACAAAUAGUCACAGGGCUUUAAUAAAAUACUGUGUAGCUACUUAAGACUCCUAAAUGUAUAUUUCCACCUCAGACAUCUCCAACUACUUUUUUGACUUCUUAACGUGAAUAUGUGAAAGACGCUUCAGCCUAAAUAUGGCCAGAACAAAAUUUCUGAUCUUUCUCUGCAAACCUGCUCCAUCUGCAGCCUGCCCCAUUUUAUUAGGUUGGUGCAAAAGUAAUUGUGGUUUUUUGCAUUAAUGGCAAAUUACUUUUGCACCAACCUAGUGGGUGUUAGCUCCAUUUUUUUCAUGUUAUUUAAGCAAAAAAAAAAAAAAAAAAAAAAAAAGAACAUGGAAUCCUCCUGACUCUUCUCUUUCUCUCCAACUCUGUUUCCAGGUUGUCAGCAAAUCCUGCUGUUCUGUCUUCAAAAUGUAUCCAGAAUCAGUUUAACUACUUUUCCCAUCCGUACUACCAGCAUCUUUGUCCAAGUCUCCUGCAUUUCUUGCCUGGAGUAUUGCCGUGGCCCAUGGCCUCCUAACAGAUCACUGGUCUCCUUUUCCUUCCCUGGCUUCUCUUUGAUUUUCCAUCUGCUUAACAUCAGAGUGAUCUUUUAAAAACAUAAGUCAAAUUGUGCUUAAAACCCUCCAGUGGCUUCCAUGUCACUCAGAAUAAAGGCCAGUGUUCUUAUGAUUCAUAAAACCUUACAUGAUCUGGGCCGGGCAUGGUGGUUCACGCCUGUAAUCCAGCACUUUGGUAGGCUGGGGUGGGCAGAUCACUUGAGGUCAGCAGUUGAAGACCAGCCCGGCCAACAUGGUGAAACCUUAUGUCUACUAAAAAUACAAAAAUUAGCCAGACGUGAUGGCAUGCACCUGUAAUUCCAGGUACUUGGGAGGCUGAGGCAGGAGAAUCUCUUGAACCUGGAAGGCGGAGGUUGCAUGCAGUGAGCCGAGAUCGUGCCAUUGCAUUCCAGCCUGGGGGACAGAGUGAGAUUCUGUCUACAAAUAAAUAAAUAAAUAAAAAUUAAAAAGCCCUACAUGAUCUGAUUCUCACUAACUGACCUCUUCUCCCGCUUGUCUCCCACUCGGCACUUUCCAUUCCAGCCUUCCUUACCUCCUUGCUAAUCCUUGAACGUGGCAGGCACAUUUCCAUUUUAGGUCUUUGCACUGGACUUUUUCCUCUGCCUAUAAUAUUUAUCCUACCCCCCCAGCCACCUCUUUCAGGUCUUCACUAAAAUAGCAUUUUGUCUGUGCGAUUACUCUAGUUACAAUUGCAAUCUGCAUCCUGUAUGUCUCUUGCAGUGCUCUGCAUUUUAUUUUUCCGUUGCAUCUGUUACCUUCUAAGUUACUAUUUAUUUGUCUAUUUUGUGAAUUGCCUCUCUUUCCUACCUCUGCUAGACUAUAAAUUCCUUGAGGUCGAGUAUGUUUAUUAAUGUGUCCUGAGUGCCUAGCACAUAGAAGAUGCUCAGUAAAUAUUUUUUGAAUGAAUGAAUGUAGUCUGCCUUCUCCAAUUUUUUUUUCAGUGAAUUUCCCAUAAAGCAACACAUGCAUAGUGUUUUAGCAUUUGUGGAUCUAACGUUGACUUAUCCCACCAGCAAGGGAGAAGUUCAAGAACAUUUAUAGUUUAUAAUGGAGAUAAUAAUACAGAGAGUGGUUAUGAGAAUUAAAUAGGGUGCUCUCUGUAAAGUACUAAUGGAUAGGACCAGGUCACUUAACUGACAAAAAAGCCUGGCCAAGUGCCCUGAUUCACAUCUGAAUGAUGUGAAUUGUAUUCUAGAAUCUUCUCUCUUUAUAUUUCAGUUUUUAAUCAAGAGUAGGUGUGGCAUCACCUGGGAGCUUUUCAAAACAUACCUGGGUUCCCUGGUAAAUAUCAGUGAUAUACUGUUACUAUAUUUUGUUCUUUAACCAGUCUGCAAAUAUUUGUCCCUUAAUGUGGGUGAUAACUAUUUGCUCUCCCCCUUUUAAUGCCUUCUUGCUGUUUGGGACAUCUUUCAUGGCCCCUUCUAGUCUUUUUUCCUAUGAGGUUCUUGCUGAAAUAACUUCUAAGGUGAUUUUGAAAUCCUCAGAGCCACUUGGAUGCACGUAAUUGAACCUUUUACUAAAUCCACAAAAUCAAAGGAUCUCAGUCCUUUACCUUCUGUUUUCCAGACAAGAGAAUGUUGUAGUCAUCCCUACAGCAAUCCUUAUAGCAGUCAUUUUAUUUUAUUGUUUUUAAAAUACCUGAUUUUUAUUUUUUCAUAUGAAUUAUAUUAAAUAAUUAUUAUGCCCCCUCUAGUCGUCACACAAAUCUGAGAAGUGGAUGAGCACUGUAUUUGAUCUCUUGGACACUUCCCUUUAUUUUCCAUGGCUCCUCAUGUCUCAGACCCUUAAAGUAUUUGCAUUCUUUUCUUUUCUUUUUUUUUCUAAUUGUAUUUUAUUUUUACUUCCAGGAUACAUGUGCAGGACAUGAAGAUUUGUUACAUAGGUAAAUGUGUGCCAUGGUGGUUUGCUGCACUUACCAAGCAGUCAUUUUAAAGUUUUGCUUAUUGUGUUUCUAGGCUCCUUUUGUGUCCUUCAAAUCCAAGAAUAUCUCAAAAACAUCAGACUCACUUUCCUCCUCUUUCUUAAUAGAGCAAGAAACAUUUGUAGAUUUUUACUGUUGCAAUUUACUGUGCAAGCAAGUGCUGUGAUUUGCAAGAAAAAAAAGAUGAUUAUUUUAGAGAUGGUUUAUGCAACUGAAGAAUACACAAUAAAUAAAAACCAUGAUGUAUGUGUGUUUAGAAAUGGAUAAGCCCAAUAGCUGUUACCUAUACACAAAAAUGUGAAAAUUUUCUUCAACUCUACUGUCAAAAUAAUUCAAAAUAUACCUAGCUCCUUGUGUAUAUUUGAUCUCUCCUUAAUUUUUCUAUGAUGCUAUAUAAGUAAGAGCAUUCCCCAUAUUUAAUUAGGUGUAAACAUUUUAGCGGUGAUUACCAUGCACAUUGGAAAUAAAAUGUCACAAGUUCCAUUGCUUUGAAUGCAUCUGUUCUACCUGAUAAAUUUCCCUUGCCUUUGCAACUCUGAUUAGAUCUACUUUUUGUUGUCGUGAAGACUCAUUCUUUUGAAAAUAGUGCUGUUACAAAUUCAUUUUAUAUUGAACCCUAAAUAUUCAGUACUAUUGGCCAAGGCUGAAUGGAAAAAAUUGACCUAUGUAUCUUUCUGAUGAUAAAUCACAUUGCCCUCAGUUUAGGCCAUUAAUGGACAGCCCAGUUGGAAAACACAUCUCGUUUAAAGUUCUACACCUGCUUUGGAGACUCUUAGACGGUAAAGAACAGGUCCAAGAAAAGCUCAAAGAAAGCAAAUACCAGCAGCAGCAGUAGCAACAGCAGCAAGUUGCCACCAGUUUGUUAUGAAAUAAUUACCUUGAAGACUAAAAAGAAGAAGAUGGCUGCUGAUAUAUUCCCCCGUAAAAAGCCAGCCAACUCCAGCAGCACCAGCGUCCAGCAGUACCACCAGCAGAAUCUCAGUAACAACAACCUUAUCCCGGCCCCAAACUGGCAGGGUCUUUAUCCCACCAUUAGAGAGAGAAAUGCGAUGAUGUUCAAUAAUGAUUUGAUGGCAGAUGUACAUUUUGUGGUUGGGCCACCAGGUGGGACUCAACGGUUGCCAGGACACAAAUAUGUUUUAGCUGUUGGGAGCUCUGUGUUCCAUGCGAUGUUUUACGGAGAACUUGCAGAGGACAAAGAUGAAAUCCGUAUACCAGAUGUCGAACCUGCUGCUUUUCUCGCUAUGCUGAAAUAUAUCUAUUGUGAUGAAAUUGACUUGGCUGCUGACACAGUGCUGGCCACACUUUAUGCUGCCAAAAAGUACAUUGUCCCUCACCUUGCCAGAGCCUGUGUUAAUUUCCUGGAGACCAGCCUGAGUGCCAAGAAUGCCUGUGUGCUCCUCUCCCAGAGCUGCCUGUUCGAGGAGCCAGACCUGACCCAGCGUUGCUGGGAGGUGAUUGAUGCCCAGGCUGAGUUAGCUCUCAAGUCUGAGGGAUUCUGCGAUAUUGACUUCCAGACACUAGAAAGUAUUCUCCGUAGGGAAACUCUGAAUGCCAAAGAAAUUGUGGUUUUUGAGGCAGCUCUCAACUGGGCUGAAGUAGAAUGCCAACGACAAGAUCUGGCGUUGAGCAUUGAAAAUAAACGCAAGGUUCUAGGAAAGGCACUUUACUUGAUCCGCAUACCCACAAUGGCCCUCGAUGAUUUUGCAAAUGGUGCUGCACAGUCCGGGGUAUUAACUCUCAAUGAGACCAACGACAUCUUCCUCUGGUAUACUGCAGCCAAAAAGCCUGAGCUUCAGUUUGUGAGUAAAGCCCGUAAGGGCCUUGUCCCCCAGCGCUGUCACCGUUUCCAGUCGUGUGCCUAUCGAAGCAACCAAUGGCGCUAUCGUGGUCGCUGUGACAGCAUCCAGUUUGCAGUUGAUAAAAGAGUGUUCAUUGCUGGCUUUGGGCUGUAUGGCUCCAGCUGUGGUUCUGCAGAAUACAGUGCCAAGAUUGAACUUAAGCGGCAGGGCGUUGUCCUGGGGCAGAACUUGAGCAAGUACUUCUCAGAUGGGUCCAGCAAUACCUUUCCCGUAUGGUUUGAAUACCCAGUGCAGAUCGAGCCAGACACCUUCUACACAGCCAGUGUGAUACUGGAUGGCAAUGAACUCAGCUACUUUGGACAAGAAGGCAUGACAGAAGUUCAGUGUGGCAAAGUGACUGUCCAGUUUCAGUGCUCCUCAGAUAGCACCAAUGGCACUGGGGUACAGGGAGGGCAGAUCCCUGAACUUAUAUUCUAUGCUUGAAAACUCACUUCCUGAAGCAGCUUGAGCUCCAAAGUGCACAUCUGGUUCCAACUUGCCUGAUGCUUAGCUCAUCUGCAAAUAUGUGAUCAGUGCCGGUAAUUUGUAAUGAAUGAAGCGGUAGGCAGGUUCUAAUUUCUUUUAACCUUUUAAUUAUGUACAGGCAAAAAUGCAGCAUUCCGCUUUUAACUAUCUGCUUAAAAGAGCUAACGUUCUUAUUAAGGCUUUGUGGUUUUUAGAGUUGCAUCUAUGAACCUGGGGAGAUUAUGUGCUUUCCCAAGCGUUCCACCACCCUCUCAGUUUUGUCCCUCUGAAGAUAAUUUUGGAUCACCUUGAAUUUCCUUUUGGACGUUAUUUGAUGAACAGAAAUAAAGUGAUAACAAGAGUUAUUUUUAAACAGAACUCCUCUUACCCCCCAAAACAGAUAAACCUCAGUGUACAAUUUUGAAAGAAGUUUUGCCUUGUAAUGAGUAAUAAUUUAGAAAGUAGACAGUGGUUGUGUUUGGCUCUCGUUUUAUUCCUUUUACAUUUGUUGCUUCUGGGAUUUAAAAAAUUACUAAAUUCAUAAGAUAGUUAGGUAUUAAACACUUCAGAAUAUCAAUGUAAAAUUGGAAAAUAAGGAACUGGGGGCAUUUGUUUAGGCCAUGACUUCUACAAGCAGAUUUCUUUUCUUUUAGUUUAGAAGACAAAAAAUUUCAAUACAGAUACUUCUUUUAGAAGUAAAUUUUUAGAUUUUAUUGUCAGUAGAAAAAAGUUAAACUCCUACUAAUUUAAACUAAGACAGUUUAAAAAGGAAGCCUGAAAAAGACUCAUACUACAAAUAAUUUAAUUGAUGGCAUAUAAGAAUAUGCAGUUUGAAAAAGCCAAACUCUUCUCUCCACUUAGCUUUUGAUCCCCACUGUUUGCUUAUUUGUAUAAGUCAUACUGUGUAGAAUUUCUAUUUUCUUUUUCCCCAUUAAAAGAGGACCAAACAAUUCUUUAUACAAAUGGAGUAGCAACUAGUUUUGUAGCACUACAUUUAAUGUAAUGAGAUACCUUUGUUCAUUUUUUUAAAUUUGAAAUAUACUUUACCUGAUCCACUUUGAUUGUAUACUAUAUUCUUUGUUAAUUUUAAUUUUGUCCUGUUCCUAGACUGCUAGAAUCUGGCCCCUGGCCAUCUUAAAGUGCCAACAUAUGCCUGCAGGGUUUAUAAAAAAUGGCCUGGAGUGACACAUUUUAUUAUACCUAAUAUUCACUGCAUCAGUAUCACAUCUAGCUCCCUUACUUGUCCACAGAUAAUGUAAACAAAGGAGGGAAAAACUUAUUAAAUUCUCCUUCGCUGCUGGCUUGUGCUGGUUUAGUGCCUGUGUCCCUGGCAGUGUCCAGUGUGUUCACUUCCAGUUGAAGUAUCCAUGUGUUUCUGGGCAGCUUUUCUGCUCAGUGUGAUCCUGAGAUGGCUUCCCCGCCGCCACCCAGAGUGUGGUCCUUGGCCGCCUCCUGCUCCUGCUCUGCAAGCCUGAAACUGGCUUGUCUGGAGCCAGGAGUUAGUCCUGGGGUGUGUGUGUGCCUGCGCACCCAUGCGCAUGCAAGUGUGUUUGCCAGCUCAGGAGCUGUCUCCUCUCUACCUGGCUAGUAAGAGGUGGGACAGUAAUGGUCCUCCUGCUGGCCCCAGCAAGGCCCAUGAGUGACUGCCCUGACGUAUUCACUGUGCCUCUGGGCCACUUCUUCCCCUGUAGAUGUGGGCUUGUUGCCUUCAGCCGGCUUCCCUGAGGGAGGAGAACACUGGAUUAUUGGAAAUGUUUUAAUCACUCUUGCCAUUACCUACAUCUAUUAGCAUAGAUGAUGAAAAGCUGUUACUGGUGAUUAUAGAUGAGUAUUUCCAGGACAACGUUCUAAAAGUACAAUUAUUUCUUAUUGGGGAGAUUACAGGUAGUUUGGCAAAGCAUUGAAGUACAAAGGUACAUUUUCAAUUAAAAAGCACACUUCUACAAAAGAUUUGGUUUUUAAAUUAUGGUUACACAUUUCAGUAACUCAUAGCUGCUGUGCAAAUUGGUAGACCUUAUAAGAAGGCACUUGUUUGUAAGCCAGAGAAGAAACUUUAAUUGCAUCCUAUCAGAUUGUUGAGGUGGGUGUGAUAGUCUUCAGGUGCAGUGCGUUCAUUCACUAACGCUCACUGUCAGUGCCCAUGUUUGCUAGCUGCCUCCAUGUGACUAGUGAGCUGCUGGUGAAAGUCGUGUGAAAUCCUGUACACUGUGUAUAGAAUAAUGUAAUUUUAUGUUAAUUGUUAUUACUUUAAAACAUAUCUACCAUCUGAUUGGCUGGUACCGAGAGCUGUGGGUAAAAUUUGAAAAUUGUAUUUAGAAUAAGAAAUUUUACAUUUUAAACCCUAUUGUCCUUUAUGCAUUUUCAAUGAAAUGGAAUGAAGGCUAAUAUGCUUGCUUUAUUUACUUUUGUAAUCUUGGAUUUUGUAGCUUUUAAAACUAGAAACCAUUGUUCUAACAAAGCAGGCAACUUUAUUCUAUAAACACAACUUUAUUAAGCAGAAUACACUGUAGAUGCUUUUCCCCAACGUAUCUGGCUGGCAGUCUUUGUCGUUGUUCAUUCUGGGGAUAAAGGGGAACUAGGCUAGCAGUUCUAAUGUGACAUUCUUUAAGCAUAUCUUAAAAUAGUAUUUAAGUAAAUGGUCUAAUUUCUACAUAAUUAUUGCACUGAACUUUUUUGUUUAUUAAGGUGUUUAAAUAAGCUCAGCUAAUUCAAGACACUGUAGCCACUUGUGCAUCAGUGUGCUUGAAUUUAGUAGCUUACAGCAUUAUUUAUGAAGGAAAAAAUACAUAAAUAUGAAGUACCUCAUGUUGAAUGUUAUUGUACUGUAUUUUUAAUGUAACAGUGCAGAUCUUGUUAGACACAUGAAUGUGUAUAAUCAUGUUAAAUGCAAAUAAAACUAGUUCAUAGA